CCUCCAUCACCAAUAGAAACCAGGCGGGGCCAGCUGACCCCAGAGCAACACCUCCAUCACCAAUAGAAACCAGGCGGGGCCAGCUGACCCCAGAGCAACACCUCCAUCACCAACAGAAACCAGGCGGGGCCAGCUGACCCCAGAGCAACACCUCCAUCACCAACAGAAACCAGGCCGGGCCAGCUGACCCCAGAGCAACACCUCCAUCACCAACAGAAACCAGGCGGGGCCAGCUGACCCCAGAGCAACACCUCCAUCACCAACAGAAACCAGGCGGGGCCAGCUGACCCCAGAGCAACACCUCCAUCACCAACAGAAGCCAGGUGGGGCCAGCUGACCCCAGAGCAACACCUCCAUCACCAACAGAAACCAGGCGGGGCCAGCUGACCCCAGAGCAACACCUCCAUCACCAAUAGAAACCAGGCGGGGCCAGCUGACCCCAGAGCAACACCUCCAUCACCAACAGAAACCAGGCGGGGCCAGCUGACCCCAGAGCAACACCUCCAUCACCAACAGAAACCAGGCGGGGCCAGCUGACCCCAGAGCAACACCUCCAUCACCAACAGAAACCAGGCAGGGCCAGCUGACCCCAGAGCAAUGGCCCUUCUGUACUCUCAUUGGUUCCCUAGAGGGCCACUGGCAGGACAAGCCUAUGCCUUGGCCAUGCUGCUCAGGUGCUGGUCUAAGGAGACCCUUCCUGUCCUGAUGCCUGGCCCCAUUUCCACUUUCUUCGAGGGCCACACACACAGAGGGGCCUGCUGAGCUACAGUUGCUGCUGUGCAACAACUCCACUCCUAGGGGAUAGCGGGGGGCCAUUAGGACACAGGUGCUGGUGCCACGGCAACUCGGUUUAGAGCAUGUGGGCUUUGCAGUCAGGACAUGCCCUAUCCUGUCCAGUCUUACCUGUGAAGGCCACACCUCUUCCUACCUGUUGGCAUUGUCAGGACUAGUGAGGGGAGGAGGCCCUGGGGGAGGCUGAUCAGCAGCCCCUUCCUGCUCCCGCUCUGCAGGGCCACACCAGCCCCACCCAUGCCCACCAUCACCUUCUGUAAGAGACCCUGGCCUGCUGCAGCAAACAAGUUAAUUCCCUCCCAGAAGAUAGGGAGGCCUCUCCCCACCACCUGCCCUGCAUCCUCCUUCACAGACCAGCCUCCAGGAAGCGCCUCUUGUUGGAAUCAGCCCCACUUUUAGAGUGUUAACACCUUUAAUUAGGGACUCACCAGGGCGAUGCCCUUGCAGUCAGGGAGUCCCGUGGGUGAGAGUGGGCUGCCCUGGGGAGCUGCAGGGAGUGGAGAGUGAGGCCACAGGGAGGGACGUGAGGCAUGAGGGGAGGUGGACUCAACCUGUGGGCCCUGAGCCCCUCAGUAAUGGCCCCUCAGGUUCUAGAAGGCUCACUCUGGCACAGUGAAGAGGGGGCAGAUCUAGAAGGAGGAAGGAAGAGAAGAGGGAGGGAAACAGGCACUGCCUGAGUGCAUUCUUUCUAAGAGGCCAGGGCAGGAGACCCUCCAAUCCCUCGGGCACCAAAGGAAUGAGUAUCCCUGGCUCUGCAUGUGGGGAUCCAGGCUAGGGGAGGCCCGCGCCUCCACCACCAUGGCACAGUUCCAGGAAGGCAGGCUGGGGAUGUGGACCGGGGCUCUCUGACCCCCAGGCAGAUUUUUGGGGGUUUACCAAGCUGCACUUUAGUAUAAGGGAGUUUGUGGCAUUUGAGUGCUGUGGCUGUGGCGACUGUGGGAGGAGGAACAUUUCAGGGCACUGAGGACACGGAGUUCUUUCUCAGAAAGGUCCCUGCCUGUGCCGGGGCCUGGUGAAGGGCACAGCCCACGAGGCUUCUGCAACUCCUGCCGCUGGAGGGCCUGUAUCCCAUUUCUUCCCAGCCCCACGGUCAGAGACACCAUGCUGGUGGUGUGAAGGCGCCUGUGGUGGGCGGAUUUACACCCCGGAUUUUGGCAGCGCGAACUUCUCCAUGCUUGCACAGCUCUUUUGAUCAAAGCCGCCUUUUUCUGGGAUGCCACACAGCAGGUUGGCUCCUUGGAGCUGGAUGUGAGAUGGUUUCAGUAAGUGACCUGUUGAGCACCGUGACUCUGAUUUGUACAGAACGAAGCAGGGCCCGAAGCUGGACCUGGCAGAUGUUGGAGGCCCCUGGAAAUACUGGGAAGCGUGAAGGGCAGGAGAUGCUCCUUCCUCUGUGGCGGGGCCUCCAGGUCACCCGAGUGUGGGUGACUCACACCUCAGCUACCCGGGGGUCUGCGCCUCGGAGUCCUAUCCCCCAGACAGUGGUAAAAUGCCAGACAUGUUUCCUCCUUUCUCCUCCCACUCAAUAAUGACUUAUGCAAAAAAGGGAACGGAAGCAUGGACACACACGUGAUAUGACUUUCAGUGACUUUUUCAACUUUUUCAGUCCAGCAUUUGGAAUGCGAUGACAACUGGUGCAUUAUUUUAAGUUUUUAAAAAUAUAAUUACAGAAAUGAACACACGAGCCAUACAGAAAAUUUGGAAACACAGAAAAGAACAGGAGGAGGAAACGAUCCCAAGCCUGCUGCUCACGAAUAACCACCUUUCACAUGUUCUUUAUCCAGGGCAGACAUUUCACAAGAGGAUGGCCACUGUGUCCAAGACAUUUGUAGCACGAUUUUACCACUCAGCAAUGUAUCCACAGCAGCUUUCAUGCCUGUGAACAUGACUCCACUGCAUGCUUUUACGGCCACAUGGCAUUACCUCAUACGCACAUCAGCAUUCAUUGAGCAAGCUCUUGCCACUUAACUGUCAGUUGUUUCCAAUUACUCAUUAUCAUACAUAAUGCUGUGAUGAACAUCAUACCGUACAAACACGACUGUGCACAAGUUGGAUUAUGCGCUGAGGAUGAAUUCUGAGAAGUGGAACCCAGCAUCUUAGCUGUGCUCUGUUAACUCCAGUGACACCCCAGCUCUGCACAGGAUCAACCUCCUGGCAAACUCAGCCUCGUUAGGCAAGUCCAGGACCCCCAGAGGACCAGGAGACUCCCCAAAACUUCCUGUCCCCGCAUGCUGAUGACCAGGGGCCCUUUGGAGCCCACCUUCCAUUUAGUCCGCAUGUCUGCUUAACCCUGAGGCCUUUGCUUUUUGCACUGGGAGACAAAGCAGAGACCUUCGGAUUCUCAGCAAGCCUCCACCAGGCUCCUGGCGUUGCCCUCCUCGAGCUGCACCCAACGUUCAUUUUUCAUGCACGGCCAUCGGUAGAGCUGCCUGGAUGAUGAGGAGAUGAAGACCCUGAAUCAGUCCGGGCAGUUCACGUCAAGACCUGGGGCCUGCCCCGCAGAGGGGCCUGAACCAUCCACCUCCCCCUGCAGCUUGGACAUCGACUGUCCUGGACUUGAGAAGUGCUGCCCCUGGUCAGGGGGGCGCUACUGCAUGGCCCCUGCACCCCAAGCUCCAGAGAGGGACCCUGUGGGCUCCUGGUACAACGUCACCAUACUGGUGAAAAUGGACUUCAAGGAACUCCAGCAAGUGGACCCCAGGCUCCUGAACCACAUGCGCCUUCUGCAUUCCUUGGUCACCAGCGCCCUGCAACCAAUGGCCUCCACCGUCCACCACCUGCACUCAGCCCCUGGGAACGCCUCCACCACAGUGUCGCGGCUGCUACUGGGCCUGCCACGGCCACUGCCUGUGGCUGACGUCUCCACCCUGCUGGGUGACAUUGCGAAGCGUGUCUAUGAAGUGAUCAGCGUCCAGGUGCAAGAUGUCAAUGAGUGUUUCUAUGAGGAGCUCAAUGCCUGCUCUGGAAGGGAACUGUGCGCAAACCUGGAGGGCUCGUACUGGUGCGUCUGUCACCAGGAAGCUCCAGCCACGUCUCCACGGAAGCUGAACCUGGAGUGGGAAGAUUGUCCUCCAGUCAGUGACUACGUGGUCCUCAACGUCACCAGUGACAGUUUUCAAGUAUCCUGGCGUUUAAAUUCUACACAGAACCACACUUUCCAUGUCCGGGUUUACCGGGGUAUGGAGUUGCUCAGGAGCGCCAGGACACAGAGCCAGGCACUGGCAGUGGCUGGGCUGGAGGCUGGAGUGCUGUACAGGGUGAAGACCAGCUACCAGGGGUGCGGGGCCGACGUCUCCACCACGCUGACCAUCAAAACCAAUGCCCAGGUAUUUGAAGUCACAAUAAAGAUUGUAAACCACAACCUGACGGAGAAGUUACUCAACCGCAGCAGUGUGGAGUACCAGGACUUUUCUAGACAACUGCUUCACGAGGUCGAGAGCUCCUUCCCACCAGUGGUGUCUGACUUGUACCGAAGUGGGAAGCUGAGAAUGCAGAUCGUGUCUCUCCAGGCGGGAAGUGUGGUCGUGAGGCUCAAGCUCACCGUGCAGGACCCCGGGUUUCCCAUGGGCAUCUCCACGCUGGCCCCCAUACUCCAGCCCCUGUUGGCAAGCACAGUGUUCCAGAUUGACCGGCAGGGGACACGCGUGCAAGACUGGGACGAGUGUGUGGACAGCGCGGAACACGACUGCUCACCGGCUGCCUGGUGCAUCAACCUGGAGGGCUCCUACACCUGCCAGUGCCGUACCACCAGGGACGCCACCCCCUCCCGCGCAGGCCGGGCCUGUGAGGGUGACCUGGUGAGCCCCAUGGGCGGUGGACUGUCUGCGGCAACAGGGGUAACGGUCCCAGGUCUUGGCACGGGAACAGCAGCCCUCGGCCUAGAGAACUUCACCUUGUCACCCAGUCCUGGGUACCCUCAGGGCACCCCGGCAGCAGGCCAGGCCUGGACCCCAGAGCCCUCACCCAGAAGAGGGGGCAGCAAUGUGGUCGGGUAUGACAGGAACAACACAGGAAAAGGCGUGGAGCAGGAGGUGCCCAGCACUGCCCCGGGUCUGGGGAUGGACCAGGGGAGCCCCAGCCAGGUGAACCCCAGCCAGGGGAGCCCCAGCCAGGGGAGCCUCAGACAGGAGAGUACCAGCCAGGCGAGCCCCAGCCAGAGGAGCACCAGCCAGGGGAGCCCCAGCCAGGUGAACCCCAGCCAGCGGAGCACCAGCCACGCGAACUCCAGCCAGGGGAGCCCCAGCCAGGGGAGCCCCAGCCAGGAGAGCCCCAGCCAGGGGAGCACCAGCCAGGCGAGCCCCAGCCAUAGGAACACUAUCGGGGUGAUAGGCACCACCUCCUCCCCGAAGGCUACUGGGUCAACCCACAGCUUCCCUCCUGGGGCCACAGAUGGCCCACUGGCCCUCCCUGGACAGCUACAGGGAAACUCCAUCAUGGAGCCACCCUCCUGGCCUUCCCCUACUGAGGACCCCACCGGCCACUUCCUGUGGCAUGCCACCCGUUCCACCCGGGAAACACUUCUGAAUCCCACGUGGCUGCGAAAUGAGGACAGUGGACCCUCCGGUUCUGUAGACCUGCCAUUGACCUCCACCCUCACAGCUCUGAAGACCCCCGCCUGUGUUCCUGUCUCCAUUGGGAGGAUCAUGGUCUCCAAUGUGACCAGCACCGGCUUCCACCUGGCAUGGGAGGCGGAUCUUGCUAUGGACUCCACCUUCCAGCUCACUCUGACUUCCAUGUGGAGCCCUGCUGUGGUCCUAGAGACCUGGAACACGAGUGUGACACUGUCGGGGCUGGAGCCUGGGGUCUUGCACCUGGUUGAGAUCAUGGCCAAAGCAUGUGGGAAAGAAGGUGCCAGAGCUCAUCUGAAAGUGAGGACAGCAGCCCGGAAGCUCAUUGGAAAGGUCAGAAUCAAAAAUGUCAGGUACUCAGAAUCCUUUCGCAACGCAAGCAGCCAGGAGUAUCGAGAUUUCCUAGAACUAUUCUUCAGGAUGGUGCGGGGCUCCCUGCCAGCCACCAUGUGUCAGCACAUGGACGCUGGUGGGGUCAGGAUGGAAGUCGUCAGCGUCACCAACGGCAGCAUCGUGGUGGAGUUUCACUUGCUGAUAAUCGCAGAUGUGGAUGUCCAGGAGGUGUCAGCUGCAUUUCUCACCGCCUUCCAGACCGUGCCUCUGCUGGAGGUGAUCAGAGGCGACACCUUCAUACAGGAUUACGAUGAGUGUGAAAGGAAGGAGGACGACUGUGUGCCGGGGACAUCCUGUCGAAACACCCUCGGGUCUUUCACUUGUAGCUGCGAGGGAGGAGCCCCCGACUUCCCUGUGGAAUAUUCUGAGAGACCCUGUGAAGGUGACUCUCCUGGCAAUGAAACCUGGGCCACCAGCCCAGAGAGGCCUCUCACCACAGCAGGGACCAAGGCUGCCUUUGUGCAAGGCACCAGCCCCACCCCCCAAGGCCUGCCCCAGCGGCUGAACCUGACCGGAGCAGUCAGGGUGCUCUGUGAGAUCGAGAAGGUGGUUGUCGCCAUCCAGAAGCGCUUCCUGCAGCAGGAAUCCAUCCCCGAGUCCUCGUUGUACCUCAGCCACCCCUCCUGCAACGUGAGCCACAGCAAUGGCACACACGUGCUCCUGGAGGCCGGCUGGAGCGAGUGUGGGACCCUCAUGCAGAGCAACAUGACGAACACCGUGGUGAGGACCACGCUGAGGAACGACCUGUCCCAGGAGGGCAUCAUCCACCACCUGAAGAUCCUGAGCCCCAUCUACUGCGCCUUCCAGAAUGACCUGCUGACAUCCUCCGGCUUCACCCUGGAGUGGGGGGUUUACACCAUCAUCGAGGACCUCCACGGCGCUGGGAAUUUUGUUACCGAAAUGCAGUUGUUUAUCGGAGACUCUCCCAUACCUCAGAAUUAUAGCGUGUCUGCCAGUGACGAUGUCAGGAUCGAAGUGGGGCUCUACAGGCAGAAAAGCAACCUCAAGGUGGUCCUGACGGAGUGCUGGGCAACCCCGUCUAGCAACGCCCGGGACCCCAUCACCUUCAGCUUCAUUAACAACAGCUGCCCUGUGCCCAACACAUACACCAACGUGAUUGAGAACGGCAACUCCAAUAAGGCCCAGUUCAAGCUGAGGAUCUUUUCCUUUAUCAACGACUCCAUCGUCUACCUGCACUGCAAACUCCGCGUCUGCAUGGAAUCCCCCGGAGCCACGUGCAAAAUCAAUUGCAAUAACUUUCGGUUGCUGCAAAAUAGUGAAACCUCUGCCACACACCAGAUGUCCUGGGGACCCCUCAUCCGGUCUGAAGGUGAGCCUCCUCAUGCAGAAGCAGGCCUGGGUGCCGGUUAUGUGGUCCUUAUUGUGGUGGCCAUCUUCGUGCUGGUGGCGGGAACAGCCACCCUUCUGAUCGUGCGCUACCAGAGAAUGAAUGGGAGAUACAACUUUAAAAUCCAGUCCAACAACUUCAGCUACCAGGUGUUCUACGAAUAGGAGGCGCAGGCUGACAGGAAGGUCGCCGUGAGUCAAGCUGCCUCCAGAACCUCAGAGCUUCCCUGGUGGGCUCCCCCGGGAUCCCCAGUGUCUCUCUGCACCUCCACCCAUCCCUCGGUUCUUAACUCUUCAAGCCUUAACGGAGGUCUGCUCUGACGGGUGGGCUCUGCCAGAGCCCGGGUGAGCCCAGAAAGGAAGACAGCAGCCACCGUCUGUCCCGAAGAGGCAGGCCGUCCUGUAGGUCCUAGAGGAGCCACAGCCCAGGGGCAGAUGAAGGGGCUGCGGAAGACGGGGGCAGUCCUGGGGGUGCUGCGGCUACACCACCACCCGCGCGGCCCCCGCAGCCUAGACCUCCCAGGCCUGUGACCCUCCACACCAGCCCUCAGAACCCUCCUGGGCUUGCCCUCCCUUGGCGUCCGUCACCCUUUGGCAAAUAUAGAAUAUUUCACAUUCUCAGAGAGACCCGACCGCGCUCUUGAUGCUCUUUCGAAAAUAGGUCAGUCUUAGAAAUACACUGCUAAUGUUAUUUUUAGUGGAUGUUUAUGCUGUUUGACUUUUCUCCUGUGUACCAAGGUAUUGCUUUUAUUUACACGACAGCGACUCAAAAGGCACUCGAUUAAUGUGACAACCUUUUCAAUAAGCAGAAAUAACGUAGGUACACAUCACUCUUUACAUUUUUCUAAGCAUUUUCACAGCCGUUUCUUCAUAUAAUCCGACCACAGUGGGAGGUGUGAUUUACCCAUUACACAAUGAGAAACCAGAGGAGCCGAUGAGUUACUUAAUUGAGGUCACAGAAUGAAUUAGCAAGAAAAUGGUUCUAAAAUCUAAGUAUUUUAGUCUAGAAUUUUCUCCAUUACAUCAUCCUAAGAGAUAAUGCUCUGUACUUCAUUUGAAAUAAACUGGAAUUGUAUUAGAUAGCUCA